GUGGUUGAGGAUGGGCUGGCGGCGGGUCCGGGUCCGCUGCCUGGCGCUGCGGGCGGCGGGCCAUGGUGGUUUGGAUUGAGCCGGGCCCGGCCGGGGCGCCGAGUCGGAGGGGGUGGCAGUGAGCGGCGGCAGAGGCUACGGGGCUCGGUUUGGCUGACUGGGGAGUCGGCAGGCGGCAGGUCUUUUGUGGGGAUGAGCCAGGGUGCAAGGAGAGUACAAUACUCCAGUUACCGAAUUGAAACCAUCCCUGCAGUGGAGCAGCCUCCUCCAGUUUCUGUUGGGUUUUGAGCUACCUGUUAAAUAAGUCAGUGGGAUUGUCAAGGACAAAGCCCUCCCUGGCUGCCUCAGGGCAAAAUCAGGAACCAUGCGAGGCCAGCGGAGCCUGCUGCUGGGCCCGGCCCGCCUCUGCCUCCGCCUCCUUCUGCUGCUGGGUUACAGGCGCCGCUGUCCACCUCUACUCCGGGGUCUAGUACAGCGCUGGCGCUACGGCAAGGUCUGCCUGCGCUCCCUGCUCUACAACUCCUUUGGGGGCAGUGACACCGCUGUUGAUGCUGCCUUUGAGCCUGUCUACUGGCUGGUAGACAACGUGAUCCGCUGGUUUGGAGUGGUGUUCGUGGUCCUGGUGAUCGUGCUGACAGGCUCCAUUGUAGCUAUCGCCUACCUGUGUGUCCUGCCUCUCAUCCUCCGAACCUACUCAGUGCCACGACUCUGCUGGCAUUUCUUCUAUAGCCACUGGAAUCUGAUCCUGAUUGUCUUCCACUACUACCAGGCCAUCACCACUCCGCCUGGGUACCCACCCCAGGGCAGGAAUGAUAUCGCCACCGUCUCCAUCUGUAAGAAGUGCAUUUACCCCAAGCCAGCCCGAACACACCACUGCAGCAUCUGCAACAGGUGUGUGCUGAAGAUGGAUCACCACUGCCCCUGGCUAAACAAUUGUGUGGGCCACUAUAACCAUCGGUACUUCUUCUCUUUCUGCUUUUUCAUGACUCUGGGCUGUGUCUACUGCAGCUAUGGAAGUUGGGACCUUUUCCGGGAGGCUUAUGCUGCCAUUGAGAAAAUGAAACAGCUCGACAAGAACAAACUACAGGCGGUUGCCAACCAGACUUAUCACCAGACCCCACCACCCACCUUCUCCUUUCGAGAAAGGAUGACUCACAAGAGUCUUGUCUACCUCUGGUUCCUGUGCAGUUCUGUGGCACUUGCCCUGGGUGCCCUAACUGUAUGGCAUGCUGUUCUCAUCAGUCGAGGUGAGACUAGCAUCGAAAGGCACAUCAACAAGAAGGAGAGACGUCGGCUACAGGCCAAGGGCAGAGUAUUUAGGAAUCCUUACAACUACGGCUGCUUGGACAACUGGAAGGUAUUCCUGGGUGUGGAUACAGGAAGGCACUGGCUUACUCGGGUGCUCUUACCUUCUAGUCACUUGCCCCAUGGGAAUGGAAUGAGCUGGGAGCCCCCUCCCUGGGUGACUGCUCACUCAGCCUCUGUGAUGGCAGUGUGAGCUGGACUGUGUCAGCCACGACUCGAGCACUCAUUCUGCUCCCUAUGUUAUUUCAAGGGCCUCCAAGGGCAGCUUUUCUCAGAAUCCUUGAUCAAAAAGAGCCAGUGGGCCUGCCUUAGGGUACCAUGCAGGACAAUUCAAGGACCAGCCUUUUUACCACUGCAGAAGAAAGACACAAUGUGGAGAAAUCUUAGGACUGACAUCCCUUUACUCAGGCAAACAGAAGUUCCAACCCCAGACUAGGGGUCAGGCAGCUAGCUACCUACCUUGCCCAGUGCUGACCCGGACCUCCUCCAGGAUACAGCACUGGAGUUGGCCACCACCUCUUCUACUUGCUGUCUGAAAAAACACCUGACUAGUACAGCUGAGAUCUUGGCUUCUCAACAGGGCAAAGAUACCAGGCCUGCUGCUGAGGUCACUGCCACUUCUCACAUGCUGCUUAAGGGAGCACAAAUAAAGGUAUUCGAUUUUUAAAGAUA